AGACCCGGGGAGAGGCCGCUGCGCGCGGAGCCCGAGCCCGGAGCGGCCGACGCCCGCCUCGGCGCGCACAUCCCGCGGGGCCCGGCCGGGUGGUGAGUGCGGGGCUCGGGGCCAGGGCGGCGAGGAACGGGGCUCCCGAGGUGGAACGGGCCGGGGCCCCGAUCCCGCCGGGCAGGGGCGGCCUGGGUGAGUGGUGGGCGGCUUUGGUUUUGAGAGUUGGGACCACACUUCUCCGCGCGAAGGGAAACUCUGGCGACUCCGCCUGGAACGCGAUUGGGAGACUGAGGAGGUGGAGCUGCUCCUCCGCGCCCCCUCCUCGCCGUCGCCGCCGGGGACCGGCCGGCCCCUUCCCCGCCCUCCCAGGGCCAGUGAUGGGGUCCUCGCCUCGGGGUCUGGGGGUUGGGGAGGGUCAAGGACGAGCCGAGUGGGGAGGUCGGGGCUUCCCCUCAGUAGUAACAGCCCUUUCUGGCUGCUCCCGGUGGGACUGACAAAGGCGGACCUCGAGCCUCCUGACCCCCGGGCGGGUGGGGGGGACCCUCCUCUCCACACACAGACAUAUUAAGUGGGUGAUCGAUGAGCGCCUUGGGUCAUCGCAGGUGCCUGGUAAAUGGUGGAUCUCCCCACCCCUCCUCAACACACAGAAAACAGGGCGGGCAGCGGGCACCACUGCACUGUCAAUGAAUAACUCACCUCUGUAGUGAACCCUGGGAGCUGAGCAGGAGGGUGAAACGGGAAGGCCGGUUUCCCACUAACUGGCAGGCAAGGCAAAUGUGGGCUGUCCUAUGGCCCCUCUGCAGGUGCGGAAUGGCGGGGUUUGUGAGCCCCUUUUGUUGUCGAGGACAGCUCCACGGGGGUCCGGGAGGUGCUUGCUCUACAGACAGAAGUUGGGCAGUCUUGCGCCCCCUGAAAAGGUUCAGAGUAGGGUGGCCCCAGAAGAGACUCCAGGGCAUGUGUGGGGGAGCACUGGGCACAGGCAGAGUUAGGCUUUGGCUGUGAGUCUGAGCAGGGCCUCAGAUAUUGGGAAUGGGCAGGAGAUCCUGGCUGUGUAAGUUGGGGAUGUGAGGUCUGGUUCUAGAUCAGCCUUUUCAGUCUGCCCUGGCCUGGUCAUUAAUAAAAGUGGGGCCAAUGUGUUCCCUUUGAGAGACCAAGUGGCUUGGAGGGAUUGUGGGCCCCCUAUCUCCCCUACUUGUUGGGUUUUCUUGGGUGUGAAAUGGGGGUUCGUUCACCAUACAGGGAGCAUCUGGUCUGUGCUGAAGUCUGUGUAAGUUGCUGGGGCCUCUGAAUCAGAAGCCAUACUCCCUGCCUUCAAGGAGCUUCAAGUCCAGAGUAGGAGGGUGGAACAGGGAGAAAGGUGACCCUGGUUGGCAUCACUAAUGCCAGGCACACACUGUUUCAUGUUUACUGGUCAGAGCAAUCCUGCCUCCCAUUGUACAACUAGGAAAUCUGAGGCUCGGAAAGCCUGAGGCAGAGCGGCCGUGCCUGUCAGGGUGGUGGCUAGGUGUGUCCAUUCUGUCCACCGCAUGCAGCGGCCUCCUCAGGAGCCUGGGAGGACAGGGGAGGCUCCCCAGGGAGAGGAUGGUUGGUGUAGGAGUUAAUGGGAUAGCGAGGGAGUGGGCAUUCCAGGCAGCGGCAAGAGCCUGUGCAGCGGUUGGAGGAGCCAAGCAGCCUGCAGUUCAGGCUGGCAGGAACGAAGGGCAUGUGUGGGGGAGCACUGGCAUGGAUCGGGUGGGAGAGGUGUGGACUGGAGGGGUAGGCCUUUAUCCCUCCCGCUCUGGGGUGCCCCAGAGGCUCUUGGGGGAGGGGUGUACUCAAUUCUGCUCAAGGAAAGUCCUGAGAAGUUGGGAGUUGGGAGGCUAGAUUGGAGGGGCUGGGAGCUGCUCAGUGGCCUGUGGCAGAGAUUAAGUGAAAUCCAUGUGCCUGAAAUGGAGGAGAAAAAGUCACUGCUCUUCUUUCUGUCCUCCUUCCGACACCCAUGGUAUGUGUGGAGGGGCAAGGGGUGCUAGGUCCUGAUUCACAGGGAGACUGCUGGCAGAAGCCUGACCACUUUCCCUGGAGUGGGUCAGCGGCCGACCUCCUCAGUGGCCUGGCCAGGAGCUGUUCUGAUCCCGCCCAUUUCUUCCUGUUGUCUCCUCAUCCAGUGUUUUUUUUUUGUUUUUGUUUUUAACCAUUUUUUCAUCUCCCAAGGCUCUGUCAUGCAUCAAUGCAGUUUUGAUUUCACAUAUGGGGAGUGGUUUUGUUACUGCCCCUUGAGGGCUGGAGAACUUUGGCACGCAGUAGGCUCUGAGCAAAUAUUUGUAAGCAUGUAGGAGUGAGUAUUGGUCUAACUAUGGGACCCUGUGCCCAAGGCCCAUCCCUGGCAUGCGGUGGCAGGAGAAUUGAACAGUAGCCCCUUGCAAGAGGUGGCCUCUGCCCAUCCUCAGGUGGACUCUGUCUUCCCAUGGGAAGAAACUUUCUUUCCUCAUCCCUUGGAAACUAGGUGGGGGGCUCUUGGGCAGCCUGGUCUUGCCACAGUCCUGGGAUCCUGGCCGGGUUCGAGACUUUCCCUGCUGCCCCCUUCCCCCCGCCCCCUUGGGUGGCUAACAGAGGCAGCCUUGUUCCUGCUCCCAUAGAGCUGCCCUGUUUUCUGCACACUAAAAAUGGAAACCCCCAAGCUAUUUCGGGAGCAGUGCCCAGCCAGGCUGUGACCACGGCCCCCCUGCUCCCACCGGGCUGUGGCCACAGUGUCCCGGCUUCCACCAGGCUGCUGGACCCUCCCCUGAGCCUUGUGCCCGGCCCUGUUCACUUCAGGGCAGCCUCAGGAGUACCCUGCUCAGGCCUCAUCUGCUAGGAUGAGCCGACCUGGGAGAAGCAAACGCUUGGGAUAUUUUGCACAGACAGCUUGGCAGCUGGGUGAUGGGAGGGGCUGGGCAACGUGGCCUGGGCACAGGCAAGUAGGGGAAGUGUCUCCCAGUCUGAGAUGCAUUGUCUGUCCCAGCACUUCACCAACCUUGGUGCUCCUGGCUAGAGACCACUGGGGAAGGUGGUAUUGCCAUAGUUUCUUGGUUCAGGGACUCAGGAGCCUCAGCUGGGGCCCAAGAAGGGGUCUGUGUGGAAAGCAGGCACCCAAAGUCUGGGGAGGUCCUGGGGAUGGGCCUGGGAACAGCCAGGCAUGGCACCUUCCUCCAGGACACACUCCACUUACCCCACAUCUUGGGCCCUGGCACUAUUCUGAACUGCAGGAGAGGAAAUAGCAAGAGAUGGCCUAGCUUCUACAGCUCUCUAGUACGUAGGGCUCCAACUAAGUACUCUCAAACGAGGGGAGUGUGCCUGAGUGUGCGUGUGUAUGUCUAAAUGUGAGUGGUGGUCUGAAUGUCUCGGGUGAGUGUGACAUAUGUGCCUGCAGUGUGUUUCUGUGUGGGGGAGUUGUCUCUAUAUGGAUGUGUCUUCAUGUGGUGUUUGAACAUGGGUGGCUGUGUCUGUGUGUGUCACUGUGCUGUGUGUAUAGAUGGCAUCUGCAUCUCUCUCUCUCUGUGUGUGUGUGUGUGUGUGUGUGUGUGUGUUGUAGGCAUAUACAUACAGGGUGGGUGGUGUGUAUGUAUCUUGCUGUGCGACUGCCUGUCUGCUGAAGCGCUGGUGGCCCUUUGGGCUGGGACAGCCCCUGGCUGUGUAGAGGGUGUGUACCUGGGUGCCUUUACAGGGUGGAGUUUGAGCAGAGAGAGGGACCUCACAGGGAGAAGGCCAUGCUGGGGGCCUGGCUGGGCCCUGCCAGCCACGGGGCUCCUUCCUAGCUGACCUUUCCCAGGCCCCUCGGGUGCCUGGCUCUGCUGCCCUCCCCCUCCUCAUGUGGGCUCUGAGGAGGCGUCCUCUGUGGAAUGUGUUUGGUGGCCAGGGGCCAGGCUGGGCCCAGCUCCACCAGCAGGCUGGGCGGUGGGGAGGGGGUGCUUCUGUGCUGCCUCCCCGGUGGGGAGCCCAGGGCUUCCACGUGCCUGCAGCCCAGGCCCCGGCUUCACACUCGGCUUUCCCGCCUGCUAGGUGACUCCCACACGGGUCAUGCUGUUGUCUCCUGAUCCAGCCGGCCCUGCCAGGUGACCAUGCCUGCUCUGGGCCCAGCUCUUCUCCAGGCUCUCUGGGCCGGGUGGGUCCUCACCCUCCAGCCCCUUCCACCAACUGCAUUCACUCCCAAUGGCACGUAUCUGCAGCACCUGGCAAGGGACCCCACCUCAGGCACCCUCUACCUGGGGGCUACCAACUUCCUGUUCCAGCUGAGCCCUGGGCUGCAGCUGGAGGCCACAGUGUCCACCGGCCCUGUGCUAGACAGCAGGGACUGCCUGCCACCUGUGAUGCCUGAUGAGUGCCCCCAGGCCCAGCCUACCAACAACCCGAAUCAGCUGCUCCUGGUGAGCCCAGGGGCCCUGGUGGUAUGCGGGAGCGUGCACCAGGGGGUCUGUGAACAGCGGCGCCUGGGGCAGCUCGAGCAGCUGCUGCUGCGGCCAGAGCGGCCUGGGGACACACAAUAUGUGGCUGCCAAUGAUCCUGCGGUCAGCACGGUGGGGCUGGUAGCCCAGGGCUUGGCAGGGGAGCCCCUCCUGUUUGUGGGGCGAGGAUACACCAGCAGGGGUGUGGGGGGUGGCAUUCCACCCAUCACAACCCGGGCCCUGUGGCCGCCCGACCCCCAAGCUGCCUUCUCCUAUGAGGAGACAGCCAAGCUGGCAGUGGGCCGCCUCUCCGAGUACAGCCACCACUUCGUGAGUGCCUUUGCACGUGGGGCCAGCGCCUACUUCCUGUUCCUGCGGCGGGACCUGCAGGCUCAGUCUAGAGCUUUUCGUGCCUAUGUAUCUCGAGUGUGUCUCCGGGACCAGCACUACUACUCCUAUGUGGAGUUGCCUCUGGCCUGCGAAGGUGGCCGCUACGGGCUGAUCCAGGCUGCAGCUGUGGCCACGUCCAGGGAGGUGGCGCAUGGGGAGGUGCUCUUUGCAGCUUUCUCCUCGGCUGCACCCCCCACUGUGGGCCGGCCCCCAUCGGCGGCUGCUGGGGCAUCUGGAGCCUCUGCCCUCUGUGCCUUCCCCCUGGAUGAGGUGGACCGGCUUGCUAAUCGCACGCGAGAUGCCUGCUACACCCGGGAGGGUCGUGCUGAGGAUGGGACCGAGGUGGCCUACAUCGAGUAUGAUGUCAAUUCUGACUGUGCACAGCUGCCAGUGGACACCCUGGAUGCUUAUCCCUGUGGCUCAGACCACACGCCCAGCCCCAUGGCCAGCCGGGUCCCGCUGGAAGCCACACCAAUUCUGGAGUGGCCAGGGAUUCAGCUAACAGCUGUGGCAGUCACCAUGGAAGAUGGACACACCAUCGCUUUCCUGGGUGAUAGUCAAGGGCAGCUGCACAGGGUCUACUUGGGCCCAGGGAGCGAUGGCCACCCAUACUCCACACAGAGCAUCCAGCAGGGGUCUGCAGUGAGCAGAGACCUCACCUUUGAUGGGACCUUUGAGCACCUGUAUGUCAUGACCCAGAGCACACUUCUGAAGGUUCCUGUGGCUUCCUGUGCUCAGCACCUGGACUGUGCAUCUUGCCUUGCUCACAGGGACCCAUACUGUGGGUGGUGCGUGCUCCUUGGCAGGUGCAGUCGCCGUUCUGAGUGCUCGAGGGGCCAGGGCCCAGAGCAGUGGCUAUGGAGCUUCCAGCCUGAGCUGGGCUGUCUGCAAGUGGCAGCCAUGAGUCCUGCCAACAUCAGCCGAGAGGAGACGAGGGAGGUUUUCCUAUCAGUGCCAGACCUGCCACCCCUGUGGCCAGGGGAGUCAUAUUCCUGCCACUUUGGGGAACAUCAGAGUCCUGCCCUGCUGACUGGUUCUGGUGUGAUGUGCCCCUCCCCAGACCCUAGUGAGGCCCCAGUGCUGCCGAGAGGAGCCGACUACGUAUCCGUGAGCGUGGAGCUCAGAUUUGGCGCUGUUGUGAUCGCCAAAACUUCCCUCUCUUUCUAUGACUGUGUGGCGGUCACUGAACUCCGCCCAUCUGCGCAGUGCCAGGCCUGUGUGAGCAGCCGCUGGGGGUGUAACUGGUGUGUCUGGCAGCACCUGUGCACCCACAAGGCCUCGUGUGAUGCUGGGCCCAUGGUUGCAAGCCAUCAGAGCCCGCUUGUCUCCCCAGACCCUCCUGCAAGAGGUGGACCCAGCCCCUCCCCACCCACAGCCCCCAAAGCCCUGGCCACCCCUGCUCCUGACACCCUUCCCGUGGAGCCUGGGGCUCCCUCCACAGCCACAGCUUCGGACAUCUCACCUGGGGCUAGUCCUUCCCUGCUCAGCCCCUGGGGGCCAUGGGCAGGUUCUGGCUCCAUAUCUUCCCCUGGCUCCACAGGGUCGCCUCUCCAUGAGGAGCCCUCCCCUCCCAGCCCCCAAAAUGGACCUGGAACCGCUGUCCCUGCCCCCACUGACUUCAGACCCUCAGCCACACCUGAGGACCUCUUGGCCUCCCCGCUGUCACCCUCAGAGGUAGCAGCAGUGCCCCCUGCAGACCCUGGCCCCGAGGCUCUUCAUCCCACAGUGCCCCUGGACCUGCCCCCUGCCACUGUUCCUGCCACCACUUUCCCAGGGGCCAUGGGCUCCGUGAAGCCCGCCCUGGACUGGCUCACGAGAGAAGGCGGCGAGCUGCCCGAGGCGGACGAGUGGACGGGGGGUGACGCACCCGCCUUCUCCACUUCCACCCUCCUCUCAGGUGAUGGAGACUCAGCAGAGCUUGAGGGCCCUCCCGCCCCCCUCAUCCUCCCGUCCAGCCUCGACUACCAGUAUGACACCCCCGGGCUCUGGGAGCUGGAAGAGGCGACCUUGGGGGCAAGCUCCUGCCCCUGUGUGGAGAGCGUUCAGGGCUCCACGUUGAUGCCGGUCCAUGUGGAGCGGGAAAUCCGGCUGCUAGGCAGGAACCUGCACCUUUUCCAGGAUGGCCCAGGAGACAAUGAGUGUGUGAUGGAGCUGGAGGGCCUCGAGGUGGUGGUUGAGGCCCGGGUCGAGUGUGAGCCACCUCCAGAUACCCAGUGCCAUGUCACCUGCCAGCAGCACCAGCUCAGCUAUGAGGCUCUGCAGCCGGAGCUCCGUGUGGGGCUGUUUCUGCGUCGGGCCGGCCGUCUGCGUGUGGACAGUGCUGAGGGGCUGCAUGUGGUACUGUAUGACUGUUCCGUGGGACAUGGAGACUGCAGCCGCUGCCAAACUGCCAUGCCCCAGUAUGGCUGUGUGUGGUGUGAGGGGGAGCGUCCACGUUGUGUGACCCGGGAGGCCUGUGGUGAGGCUGAGGCUGUGGCCACCCAGUGCCCAGCGCCCCUCAUCCACUCGGUGGAGCCACUGACUGGGCCUGUAGACGGAGGCACCCGUGUCACCAUCAGGGGCUCCAACCUGGGCCAGCAUGUGCAGGAUGUGCUGGGCAUGGUCACGGUGGCUGGAGUGCCCUGUGCUGUGGAUGCCCAGGAGUACGAGGUCUCCAGCAGCCUCGUGUGCAUCACCGGGGCCAGUGGGGAGGAGGUGGCCGGCGCCACAGCGGUGGAGGUGCCGGGAAGAGGACGUGGUGUCUCAGAACACGACUUUGCCUACCAGGAUCCGAAGGUCCAUUCCAUCUUCCCGGCCCGCGGCCCCAGAGCUGGGGGCACCCGUCUCACCCUGAAUGGCUCCAAGCUCCUGACUGGGCGGCUGGAGGACAUCCGAGUGGUGGUUGGAGACCAGCCUUGUCACUUGCUGCCGGAGCAGCAGUCAGAACAACUGCGGUGUGAGACCAGCCCACGCCCCACGCCUGCCACGCUCCCUGUGGCUGUGUGGUUUGGGGCCACGGAGCGGAGGCUUCAACGCGGACAGUUCAAGUAUACCUUGGACCCCAACAUCACCUCUGCUGGCCCCACCAAGAGCUUCCUCAGUGGAGGACGUGAGAUAUGCGUCCGUGGCCAGAAUCUGGACGUGGUACAGACGCCAAGAAUCCGGGUGACCGUGGUCUCGAGAAUGCUGCAGCCCAGCCAGGGGCUUGGACGGAGGCGUCGCGUGGUCCCGGAGACGGCAUGUUCCCUUGGACCCUCCUGCAGUAGCCAGCAAUUUGAGGAGCCGUGCCAUGUCAACUCCUCCCAGCUCAUCACGUGCCGCACACCUGCCCUCCCAGGCCUGCCUGAGGACCCCUGGGUCCGGGUGGAAUUUAUCCUUGACAACCUGGUCUUUGACUUUGCAACACUGAACCCCACACCUUUCUCCUAUGAGGCCGACCCCACCCUGCAGCCACUCAACCCUGAGGACCCCACCAUGCCAUUCCGGCACAAGCCUGGGAGUGUGUUCUCCGUGGAGGGGGAGAACCUGGACCUUGCAAUGUCCAAGGAGGAGGUGGUGGCUAUGAUAGGGGAUGGCCCCUGUGUGGUGAAGACGCUGACGCGGCACCACCUGUACUGCGAGCCCCCCGUGGAGCAGCCCCUGCCACGGCACCAUGCCCUCCGAGAGGCACCUGACUCUUUGCCUGAGUUCACGGUGCAGAUGGGGAACUUGCGCUUCUCCCUGGGUCACGUGCAGUAUGACGGCGAGAGCCCUGGGGCUUUUCCUGUGGCAGCCCAGGUGGGCUUGGGGGUGGGCACCUCUCUUCUGGCUCUGGGUGUCAUCAUCAUUGUCCUCAUGUACAGGAGGAAGAGCAAGCAGGCCCUGAGGGACUAUAAGAAGGUUCAGAUCCAGCUGGAGAAUCUGGAGAGCAGUGUGCGGGACCGCUGCAAGAAGGAAUUCACAGACCUCAUGACUGAGAUGACCGAUCUCACCAGUGACCUCCUGGGCAGCGGCAUCCCCUUCCUCGACUACAAGGUGUAUGCGGAGAGGAUCUUCUUCCCUGGGCACCGCGAGUCGCCCUUGCACCGGGACCUGGGUGUGCCUGAGAGCAGACGGCCCACUGUGGAGCAAGGGCUGGGGCAGCUCUCUAACCUGCUCAACAGCAAGCUCUUCCUCACCAAGUUCAUCCACACGCUGGAGAGCCAGCGCACCUUUUCAGCUCGGGACCGUGCCUACGUGGCAUCUCUGCUCACCGUGGCACUGCAUGGGAAGCUUGAGUAUUUCACUGACAUCCUCCGCACUCUGCUCAGUGACCUGGUUGCCCAGUAUGUGGCCAAGAACCCCAAGCUGAUGCUGCGCAGGACAGAGACUGUGGUGGAGAAGCUGCUCACCAACUGGAUGUCCAUCUGUCUGUAUACCUUCGUGAGGGACUCCGUAGGGGAGCCUCUGUACAUGCUCUUUCGAGGGAUUAAGCACCAAGUGGAUAAGGGGCCAGUGGACAGUGUGACAGGCAAGGCCAAAUACACCUUGAACGACAACCGCCUGCUCAGAGAGGAUGUGGAGUACCGUCCCCUGACCUUGAAUGCACUAUUGGCUGUGGGGCCUGGGGCAGGAGAGGCCCAGGGCGUGCCCGUGAAGGUCCUAGACUGUGACACCAUCUCCCAGGCAAAGGAGAAGAUGCUGGACCAGCUUUAUAAAGGAGUGCCUCUCACCCAGCGGCCAGACCCUCGCACCCUUGAUGUUGAGUGGCGGUCUGGGGUGGCCGGGCACCUCAUUCUUUCUGACGAGGAUGUCACUUCUGAGGUCCAGGGUCUGUGGAGGCGCCUGAACACACUGCAGCAUUACAAGCAGGUCCCAGAUGGAGCAACUGUGGCCCUCGUCCCCUGCCUCACCAAGCAUGUGCUCCGGGAAAACCAGGAUUAUGUCCCUGGAGAGCGGACCCCAAUGCUGGAGGAUGUAGAUGAGGGGGGCAUCCGGCCCUGGCACCUGGUGAAGCCAAGUGAUGAGCCGGAGCCGCCCAGGCCUCGGAGGGGCAGCCUUCGGGGCGGGGAGCGUGAGCGCGCCAAGGCCAUCCCUGAGAUCUACCUGACCCGCCUGCUGUCCAUGAAGGGCACCCUGCAGAAGUUCGUGGAUGACCUGUUCCAGGUGAUUCUCAGCACCAGCCGCCCCGUGCCGCUCGCUGUGAAGUACUUCUUUGACCUGCUGGAUGAGCAGGCCCAGCAGCAUGGCAUCUCCGACCAGGACACCAUCCACAUCUGGAAGACCAACAGCUUGCCUCUGAGGUUCUGGAUCAAUAUAAUAAAAAACCCGCAGUUUGUGUUCGACGUGCAAACAUCUGAUAACAUGGAUGCGGUGCUCCUUGUCAUUGCACAGACCUUCAUGGACGCCUGCACCCUGGCCGACCACAAGCUGGGCCGGGACUCCCCGAUCAACAAACUUCUGUAUGCACGGGACAUUCCCCGGUACAAGCGGAUGGUGGAAAGGUACUAUGCAGACAUCAGACAGACUGUCCCAGCCAGCGACCAAGAGAUGAACUCUGUCCUGGCUGAACUGUCCUGGAACUACUCCGGAGACCUCGGGGCGCGAGUGGCCCUGCAUGAACUCUACAAGUACAUCAACAAGUACUAUGACCAGAUCAUCACUGCCCUGGAGGAGGAUGGCACGGCCCAGAAGAUGCAGCUGGGCUAUCGGCUCCAGCAGAUUGCAGCUGCUGUGGAAAACAAGGUCACAGAUCUAUAGGAACCCAGGAGCCACGGCCUGCUGUUGCUUCAGCCUGGCCUGGGCAGCCCUGGAAGCUCGGAGGAGAGGCCACCUUCUUAGGUGCCUGUAGUGACUGACAAGCAGAGUUAGUGGAAGGUGACUCCCAGUCUCCUGGUGGCUCUGGCCUCGGCCCUGCUGGAUCCACCUCCUAGACCCGGGGCCUCAAGGCUCAUGGGGUAGUACCCAGCCUGCUCCCCGAGUCCAGCGACCCUGUGACACCGGUCUGCAGGGAGUUGGGGACUAAGGGCUUCCAGAGAGUGGCUGGAAGAGACUCCAGGCCCCUGGGGAGACUGUACUGUUCCUGAACACUGGCCUUGGCCACACUGGGAUUCGGAGAGGAAGGAGGAGAGCCCCAUGCUUCCUGUCUGCCUCCUCCACCAUCCCUGACCUCAGUUGAGCUGCCUCUGGCCUUGUUGCUGCUGCCACAUCCUAGGUCUAAGAGUUGAACGCCUCUCCUAGGCCACUACAAACUGACCCCUCAGCAGGGCUGGCUGCCACAGGGCUGCCCUGCCUCAUAGGUAGCCAUGGUGAGGGCUAUCUGCUGCAGGGGGGUCUUGGGGAGAGUGGUGACUCCAUUGACCCAGCUUUUCAUUAAAGGAUAACACACUGCA